AAAGGUGCUGGCUGCGCCCGCCGGAGAUAAGUACGCCGGCUUCGCGCGCUCCCCAGCGGCCCGCGGGAGGCGACGGACGGCGGGACGGACGGACGGACGGCAGCUUACCGGGGCCGAGGGCCAAACCCGCGAAGCGCGCGGGCUCCGACGGGCAAGCGGCGGACGGGGGCUCCGGCGAGCCCUCGGGGCCCGGGCGCCCUCUCCACUCCGGGGCGCACGGCCUCACCCCGCACACCCCCUGCACCCGCCCGGCAUGCAGCGGGCCCAGGACUGAGGGGCGGAGGCGUCUGCUCUCCGGGUCCCGCUCGGCCCCUGCCCGGCGCUCCCGGCGGUGCUCCCGGCGUCCGGCGGGCUUCCCGGCGGCGGCGCGGCGCGGGGACUUUUCGCCUCUCGCUGGCCUCUACCGAGCGCGUCUAUGAGCGCAGCGUUCCCGCCGUCGCUGAUGAUGAUGCAGCGCCCGCUGGGGAGUAGCACCGCCUUCAGCAUAGACUCGCUGAUCGGCAGCCCGCCGCAGCCCAGCCCCGGCCAUUUCGUCUACACCGGCUACCCCAUGUUCAUGCCCUACCGGCCGGUAGUGCUGCCGCCGCCGCCGCCGCCGCCGCCCGCGCUGCCCCAGGCCGCGCUGCAGCCAGCGCUGCCGCCCGCACACCCUCACCACCAGAUCCCCAGCCUGCCCACAGGCUUCUGCUCCAGCCUGGCGCAGGGCAUGGCGCUCACCUCUACGCUCAUGGCCACGCUCCCCGGCGGCUUCUCCGCGUCGCCCCAGCACCAGGAGGCGGCAGCGGCCCGCAAGUUCGCGCCGCAGCCGCUGCCCGGCGGCGGUAACUUCGACAAGGCGGAGGCGCUGCAGGCUGACGCGGAGGACGGCAAAGGCUUCCUGGCCAAAGAGGGCUCGCUGCUCGCCUUCUCCGCGGCCGAGACGGUGCAGGCUUCGCUCGUCGGGGCUGUCCGAGGGCAAGGGAAAGACGAGUCAAAGGUGGAAGACGACCCGAAGGGCAAGGAGGAGAGCUUCUCGCUGGAGAGCGAUGUGGACUACAGCUCGGAUGACAAUCUGACUGGCCAGGCAGCUCACAAGGAGGAAGACCCGGGCCACGCGCUGGAGGAGACCCCGCCGAGCAGCGGCGCCGCGGGCAGCACCACGUCUACGGGCAAGAACCGGCGGCGGCGGACUGCCUUCACCAGCGAGCAGCUGCUGGAGCUAGAGAAGGAGUUCCACUGCAAAAAGUACCUCUCCUUGACCGAGCGCUCGCAGAUCGCCCACGCCCUCAAACUCAGCGAGGUGCAGGUGAAAAUCUGGUUCCAGAACCGACGGGCCAAGUGGAAACGGGUGAAGGCAGGCAAUGCCAAUUCCAAGACAGGGGAGCCCUCCCGGAACCCUAAGAUCGUCGUCCCCAUCCCUGUCCACGUCAGCAGGUUCGCUAUCAGAAGUCAGCAUCAGCAGCUAGAACAGGCCCGGCCCUGAGGGUCCAGAAGGGCCAGGGCCUGGCACCCACCUGGAGAAGCCCCCGCACCCGAGGGAACCCAUGGUGGACUCCACUGUGUUUGAAGCAACAAAGUCACAGCCCAGCUGUGGCCAUCCCAAGCAAAUUGAGAAUAUAUUCACUAAAUGGGCUUAAAAGACUGCUUUUGAAGGGGCUUACAGCCACACCAGAAGACACGCUAAAUAUUUAUUAUACUAUCCUACUUUGUACAUAAAUAUCUCUAUAGACUGGAUCUCAGCUGCAGUAUUUUGAAAGUUAUAGGACUUAAUUACCCAGUAAUUUCUCCACUCAUUCCAGAAGAAAACAAAACCUCUGCUGUAAUCUGCGCGGUUAGCAGCCACCUUUCCAUACUUUUCCAAAGCCUAAUCGAUACCUAGUAGGCCGGCAAACUUCGGCCAGAGGAGGAGGUGGGUGCCCGGAGGAGGCAAGCGAGUGCGGGUAUUGGUGGCUUUGCACAAACUCCUGAUGCUCCAAAUCGACUACAGCCAGGGAGGAAACGUCUUUCCUUUACAAAUAUCUCCGGCCCGAAAAGAAGCGGUGCUCGCCUGCCGGCAGAGUGGAGGGUCCAUAAAUCAGGCUCCGGGCGUUAUCUGGCGACAGGAGCAAAAACCCAGCGAGCCCAGCCGGCUUCCCGGCAGCCCUCAGUCGGAGGCGGAGGCUGGCUGGAGCGCCCCCGGCCCCGGCACCUCCCCCUCCGGGCGGGGUCGAGGGGGCGGGACCCGGGCACCGCCCCACCCCAAGGACGCCCCGGUAGUCCGCACCACAAAGGGGGAAAACGGGAGAGGCUACGCAGGGGAGCUGGGAGUCGGUCUGCAAGGGACGGGGAGCUGCGCGCCUCCCCAUCUCGGUGGGGCGUGCCUGGUCCCCAAGCCCACUCCUGUCCCAACCCCGGCCCUGCGCUCAGAGCCCUGUCCGCUCGCUGCCGGACCCCGAAGCGCGCCGCCAGAUACUGCGGCGGACAGGCCCAGGGGCGUUCAGCGGGCCAGCGAGUGUGAGCGUGGUGCCACCAAGCCAGCAGCCCGAAGCGCGAGAGAAGCCGGGGCUUCGCCAGCCUCAGCCUUUCGAGUGGGGGAAGGAGGGGAGGCCGGUGAGCCGCUGCGAUGCAGCGGCGCUCGGCCCUCGGCGAGGUUCUCAGCCGAAGAAGGGGAAGCGCGGCCCGCCAUGGGUUAGUACUAAUAUUGACUUAAUUUUUACUACUUACAGGCCGUCACCUCCCCACGGCGGAGGGGCCUGGGGACCAAGACCUCCACCCAAACUUCAGGCGCAGGGUGAAGGCUGGGAGCGACCGAGUCACCCUUUCCCGCCGCGUUCCCAACAGUUCCGGUGGCGGAAAAUGGCCCAGACUUGGUUUUCGAGCCCAAUAAAAUAGAAGGGCCAGUCCUCCGAGGGCGUCGGCCGGCUCUGCGGGGCGCCGAGAGCCGCAGAGGCUCCUGGCCGCGCCCCGCCCAGCGCCAUGAAGCCUGGCAGGGAGGGGAUGGCGCCCGGGUCGCGCCCUGGCCUGGCGCGGGGGCCGCAAGGCCGGGAUCCCGCCCGCCAGGAAGCGCUGAGUGCAGGUUGCCGGUGAGCGCCUGCUGCUCGGGGCAGGUACCCACUGGCCACACGACGCUGCUGCAGCAUUCGAGGCCCGCAGGGACGCCGUCCCCCGACCCACACACCUGAGCCAGUCUGCGCGUGGCUGGGGGCGAAGAGUUUACCCGGGAAGGUUGGGGAGCUGCGGCCUCUGCCCCGCCGGCCCUGCGGGUCGGGGGAAGAGACCCUGGCACUCCCCGCAGAUCCUGGAGUGCCCCCCAUAUCCCCUUCCACCAUAACAGGUGUAACCCCACCCGCCUUCUCCAAAAGCCCAUGGCAGGGAUGAGGGGCAGAGGGACCCGAAGCUUUGACCGCACAAACCCGGCGGGAAAGCGAAGCCCACUAGGAACCGGAGGCCGCCGUCAGGAAGCCCCGCUCCUGGGACCGAGCUCCGGGCCCUCCCAGCCUCGAGGUCCUCGCCCUAUGGAGGCACGAGGAGGAGAGGGCCCGAGCUCCCCAAGCUGGCCGAUGCCGCCCUCCCUCCUGCUCCUCGGGGCGCUGACCCCCUCCCUCCCUAACCCCUGAGCCCCGGGGCGCCCCCGAGAGCCCGGCAGGGAGGCCAAGGCCCGGGAGACAGGCCGAGGGGAGGAAGAUAAACAAGCAGCGCUUGAUGGCCGCUGUCAUCAUGGCCGUCAUCAUGGCUUUCAUUUGGCUGCCUAAUGAGUCACAUCACAGGCAGAGAGAAAAAUUGUCAAUCGCCCGGGCCCUAAUGAAUUUUUUUGCAAAUUGUAAUCAAGCCAGGCCGUCUCAGCUGGCUGAUUAAUGAGACCCACGAGGCUCGGCCAGCACCUCAGCUUUUUAUUCCAUCCCGUCCUCCCUGCACUAAAUUAACAGCAACUUGUCUGAGCUUCAAAUUAACUCCCAAUGAUUAAUUCUGAUGGGGGGGCCUGAAGAAUAGCUUGUUCUAAUAGGCUCUGGCCUGAGAUGCUGUUGGAAAUUAAUACACUUCCCCUUUGGCUGCCGGCUUUAAUCCAAGGUUGGGUUUUGACAUCACUAUAUUUGUUGUUACAAUAAAUUCCACUUACAUCUGCAGAUCAAAUAAUUACACUUGGGAGCUCCUUGGACCUGCGCCCCCCAGCCGUGCACUGGGACGCCUCAGGGCUGCCUGCACCCCGCAGCCACCGACCCAGGCAGAGGUCGGAGGGGGGCCACAAGAACAGUCACUCCACCCAGUGACUGCCUUUGCUCCCUGGCAAGCCAGGCACCCCUGCCCCAUUGGAGAACCCAAGAAGGAGCCCAGGACUACCUUCCCAGCAGCCGGGACCCACCUGCACUGGAAGCUGCUCAAAUCCCAACCUGCGCUGGAAUUUUCGAGACUUAGUGCAUGCUUGUGCAUCCAGCCUUUGCUUCCUGUCUUCAGCCCCCUGGGUGGUUCUUUCACAGAUGCCUUGUCAGCUAAAUGGAGAGCAGGGAGUGGCCCCCCCAGGCUUUUUUGAGCCCGGGUUUGCCUCGGAGGACAUCCUGACUCUAUGGCUGUCUGUGCGUCUGGCCUUCAGCCUAGGUGCUUGUACAAGCCUGGGCACAUCGCUGGUACCUGCAUUCCAAGACACCCUUUCUCUCAGGGUCAGCACCCUCUCCCUCUUGUUUCUGUUUGUUUGAGCUUAAUGGGCUUAAUUAUUUCAGCUGCAUCUGGUGAAGCUCGCACAGGGCUUCCAAGGCUGCUCCCUCCAGCCCCAGACCUGUCUGGAACAGAGUCCCAUGUUAUGCCCCAUGGCGGGUGGUUCUAGGUGCACUGAAAGCCGGGAGUGACCUUCUAGCUUUCCGGCCUCAGGAGCCUUUGGAUCACACUCUGGUUCUCACCUCGGGGCCUUCCUAGUCCCAAGUGGCUGGAGCCCACGCAUUCAGCAGCGCGGGCAGCAGAGACCCUCUCGGGGCCCUCUUCUUUCCCCUGCUGGACUUCAGUGGCGGUGUGGCAGAGUGGCUCGCUUAUGCCCAGCCGUGGCUUCCCAGGGAAGGAGGCUCCAGUGCACACACCUAUUUCUGUCCCCAGAGACCCCAGGCAUCUGCCCAGGCAUGCACAGCCAGAGCAGGUGGCCUGCUCCGACCUUCUGGCCGCUGGGUCCUCCCAGGCAGCUUCAGCGCAGUGCUCAGGGCCCAGUUCCAGGGUAGCAGGGCUCUGGGGUCUUGGGGGAAGCUAAGGCCGGGGUUCUACAGGGACAGCCCAGACGAAGGGAGGUGGCAUUCAUCUUCAUUUUAGGCCCUUAGGGUGUAAACAGGAGAAAUAUGAUCUUGGUAACCAAACAUGAAUGCAAAUCACACCGGCAGAGUAAUAAAGCACCUGAAACCCCAACGCACAUAAGCAACACCAUAUGUAUGUAGACAACCUGCAUAAAUUAUAAAUUACAUCAUCAAAA